GAUAGAUUCUACCUUUGUCACCCAGGCGGGAGUGCAGUGGCAUGAUCUCGGCUCACUACAACCUCCGCAUCCUGGGUUCAAGCAGUUCUCCUGUCUCAGCCUCCCGAGUAGCUGAGAUUACAGGCAUGUGCCACCAGGCAUGGCUAAUUUUUGUAUUUUUAGUGGAGACAGGGUUUCACUCUAUUAGGCUGGUCUGGAACUCCCGACCUCAGGUGAUCCACGUGCCUUUGUCUCCCAAAGUGCUGGGAUUACAGGCAUGAGUGACGGUGCCCAGCCAUUCGUGACAUGUUUAUACAAAUAUAACUUUAGCAAAUAUUUAGCAUAACUAUCAAAAUUACAAAUCAUAUUAAAUUUGUAUAAAUGUAUGCAAUUUUUGGAACACGCAUAUCAACAACAUACCCAUAAAUAUAACUGAGAUGAGAUCUAAUGUCACCUCACUUGACAGUGCCCUCCCAUGCAGUAUCGCCACAUUUGACAAUGCCUGCCCAUUUAAUCUACCAAAUAAAUCGAAUCACUUAAUACCUCUACAAGAUGAGAGAUACAUUCUUUAGACUCCCCAAGGGAUGCAGCUGAAAAAAAUCCCAAAGUUAGUUUUAAGCCAAAAAGACUUGAUUUAGGAUUUUGACACUGGAGAAACCCAUCAAAGAUGUCAAGUUUGAAAACACUUGAUCAAAACAGAAUCACAGGUCACUAUUAAAAGAGUAUUAAUUUAACCAGAGACUUCCAAAGCAAUACAGAAACUUACAUGGAUAUAAAAACCCUAACCCUUUUAAAGGUCAGAUUUGCUAAGUGAUCAAAAGGGGUACUUGAAUUGAAUCGACACAGGAAGAGUGUGUACAGGGUUAUGAGUGUAGGCAGGUGGUUACUUUGGUCAUAUCUCCAUUUGCCACCUGAUUACACAUGAGAAUGGCAUCUUUACUCACCAGAAAGCCAGUAUUAUAGGAGGUGUAGGAGGCAUUCUUGGACUUGAGACAAGAACAUUGUUGUGUAGAAAUUUCAUUGACUGUGUUAAAAUUAUUCUCCAUGGGCUGGAGAACACAUAACAUGGCCUUUAGAAUGAGACGGGCAUUGAUUGGAUGCAAGGUCUCCACACUUACUAGCUGUGUGACAUUGGACAGAGUGCUUCAUCAUUCCGAGACUCAGUUUUUAAAGGAAAAACAACUAACUACCUUGCAAGCUUGCUAGCAGGUUUAAGUGUAAUAAUGUGUGGGAAUGACUGCACCGUGACUAACAUGCAGUGACAGCUUAAUUAAUGUUAACCCUUAUCAUUAUCAUAUAAGAAUGUGAGUUACAUAAGAGAGGAGUCCUGUCAGUUCGUUCUCUGCUGUGUCCCCAAGACCAUGAAUCAUGGCUGGCAUGUAGUAGGCAUUUAAUAAUAUAUGUUCAACAAGUAUUUGGCAGUCUUGGAGGGCAGAAAAGGAGGUGGGGAAGAUUUUUAAAUAACAUUUUUUAAAAAGUCACAUUGUCCUACAAUACCGAUUUUUCUUGCAUAUUUAGGAAAUUGAGGGUUUUUUUCUAAAACAUGCGGACAUAUGGGAAAUAGGAUGCAACAUUUGCACUAAUGUUUCAGACACAGUUAGAGGUUUCCAAGAGAUUUUGCGCUGGGGAGGCUGCUUGCUACAAGCUCCCAAAGCUCUGGGAGGACAUAGUAUUCAUUCCUCCCUCAGCAGAAGCGGUGAGGCAAGAAGCUCUGGGGAGCACCCAGCGUUGGACUUUUAGCAUAGUGUGUCAGGUCUUCAUAGUUUGGGCCCAGGGCACAGAGAAGUCACAGCUCUCCGGCAUCCUGUGACCUUUACCCUCUUUGCCAAGGGAAAAUGUGGCCCACCAAAGCAAGAAACUUGAGGGCAUGGGUCACCCCAGCCCUGGCAUCUGCCCAGAGCCCGAGAAGGAAGGAACAAUGAUCCUCCAGCUACCUCACGGGGCUGGCACAGGUGACCACUGCCCUGGCAUCACCCAGCUGUGUCCGGCAGCCUGAACCCCAUCUGUGGGGAUGCGAGGAGGAAAAUACAAAAGUCCUUAGGUGAACACUGAGAAGGCAGAUGCAGCAGAAACCUCCAGGCCAGAACUACCCAGUCUUGGACCUAUGGUGGAGAUAGAGCAUAGCUGGCGAUCAUGUGUACUUACACUCUAAGGUCACCUGGUUGCACUAUGGCCUCAUCUGUGGCUCUGAAAAUGAAGAUUUGGAAGGAGAUCAUCACAGCUAAUGUUUAACAAGCCCCUCCUGUGUGCCAAAUCAUUCACCCCUCACCACAACCGAAUGAGCUAAGGAUUCUCAUUAUAUAUAGUUUAUGGAGAGGGAAGUGCAGACAUAAAGAGGUGAAUUAUCUUACCCAGAUCACACAGCUGAUAAGUGGUGGAGGCAGAAUAGAAUCUAAACAGUGUGGCUCCGGAGCCCACAUGCAUUGAUUCGACAAGUGUUUAUUGAGCACCUGCCGCGGACAAGGCCUUGUGUGAUUAAAUAGGGUUAUAAUUAGUAAUAUAAAAAUGAGAAAUCACUAAUGCUUUUUAGACUUAACAUUUUGUUUUUUUGUAGGUUUCAGGCACAGAACUGUAUAUCCAAUAAUAGUGAAAUGGAUCCCACUAAUUAUGACAGAAAUGAUGAUACAUUUAAAUGACUUGGAUGUUUUAUAGGUAUGAUCUCGUGAAAUCUUGAGAGAAACUGAAUGACGAAUGAAACUAUUGUUCCUGUUUCACACAGAAGAAAACUGAGGUUAAAAGGGGUAAAGUAAUUUUGCAUGGCAUGAAGUAGAAAUUCAAAGUACAGGAAUUUGAACUUGGUUCUGUCCUUUUCUGAAGCCCUUGACCACUAUAGACUCAAACAUCACCUUGUUUUUCCACUCAUUCAACACUUUUUUUUUUAAAUUAUCUAAUAGGUUGGCACUCAUCAUGAGCCCCUGUUCUCAUUCUGCAAAUGGUGAAGCUCUCUAUUGUCCUGACCCCACAGUUCCUGUCCCAUGACCAGGGCCAGCUCACCAAGGAGCUGCAGCAGCAUGUAAAGUCAGUGACAUGCCCAUGCGAGUACCUGAGGAAGGUUAUCAAUACUCUGGCUGACCAUCAUCAUCGUGGGACUGACUUUGGUGGAAGUCCUUGGUUACAUGUCAUUAUUGCGUUUCCGACAAGUUAUAAAGUUGUCAUUACCCUCUGGAUAGUUUACCUUUGGGUGUCUCUCCUGAAGACUAUCUUCUGGUCUCGAAAUGGACAUGAUGGAUCCACGGAUGUACAGCAGAGAGCCUGGAGGUCCAACCGCCGUAGACAGGAAGGGCUGAGGUCCAUUUGUAUGCACACAAAGAAAAGAGUUUCUUCCUUUCGAGGAAAUAAAAUUGGCCUGAAAGACGUCAUUACUCUACGGAGACAUGUGGAAACAAAAGUUAGAGCUAAAAUCCGUAAGAGGAAGGUGACAACGAAAAUCAACCAUCAUGACAAAAUCAAUGGAAAGAGGAAGACCGCCAGAAAACAGAAAAUGUUUCAACGUGCGCAAGAGUUGCGGCGGCGAGCAGAGGACUACCACAAAUGCAAAAUCCCCCCUUCUGCAAGAAAGGCUCUUUGCAACUGGGUCAGAAUGGCGGCAGCGGAGCAUCGUCAUUCUUCAGGAUUGCCCUACUGGCCCUACCUCACAGCUGAAACUUUAAAAAACAGGAUGGGCCACCAGCCACCUCCUCCAACUCAACAACAUUCUAUAACUGAUAACUCCCUGAGCCUCAAGACACCUCCCGAGUGUCUGCUCACUCCCCUUCCACCCUCAGCGGAUGAUAAUCUCAAGACACCUCCCGAGUGUGUGCUCACUCCCCUUCCACCCUCAGCGGAUGAUAAUCUCAAGACACCUCCCGAGUGUGUGCUCACUCCCCUUCCACCCUCAGCGGAUGAUAAUCUCAAGACACCUCCUGAGUGUCUGCUCACUCCCCUUCCACCCUCAGCGGAUGAUAAUCUCAAGACACCUCCCGAGUGUCUGCUCACUCCCCUUCCACCCUCAGCUCUACCCUCAGCUCCACCCUCAGCGGAUGAUAAUCUCAAGACACGUGCCGAGUGUCUGCUCCAUCCCCUUCCACCCUCAGCGGAUGAUAAUCUCAAGACACCUUCCGAGCGUCAGCUCACUCCCCUUCCACCCUCAGCUCCACCCUCAGCAGAUGAUAAUAUCAAGACACCUGCCGAGCGUCUGCGGGGGCCGCUUCCACCCUCAGCGGAUGAUAAUCUCAAGACACCUUCCGAGCGUCAGCUCACUCCCCUUCCACCCUCAGCUCCACCCUCAGCAGAUGAUAAUAUCAAGACACCUGCUGAGCGUCUGCGGGGGCCGCUUCCACCCUCAGCGGAUGAUAAUCUCAAGACACCUUCCGAGCGUCAGCUCACUCCCCUUCCACCCUCAGCUCCACCCUCAGCAGAUGAUAAUAUCAAGACACCUGCCGAGCGUCUGCGGGGGCCGCUUCCACCCUCAGCGGAUGAUAAUCUCAAGACACCUUCCGAGCGUCAGCUCACUGCCCUUCCACCCUCAGCAGAUGAUAAUAUCAAGACACCUGCCGAGCGUCUGCGGGGGCCGCUUCCACCCUCAGCGGAUGAUAAUCUCAAGACACCUUCCGAGCGUCAGCUCACUCCCCUUCCACCCUCAGCUCCACCCUCAGCAGAUGAUAAUAUCAAGACACCUGCCUUCCACCCUCAGCGGAUGAUCUCAAGACACCUUCCGAGCGUCAGCUCACUCCCCUUCCACCCUCAGCUCCACCCUCAGCAGAUGAUAAUAUCAAGAUACCUGCUGAGCGUCUGCGGAUUCCGCUUCCACCAUCAGCCGAUGAUAAUCUCAAGACACCUUCCGAGCGUCAGCUCACUCCCCUUCCACCCUCAGCUCCACCCUCAGCAGAUGAUAAUAUCAAGACACCUGCCGAGCGUCUGCGGGGGCCGCUUCCACCCUGAGCGGAUGAUAAUCUCAAGACACCUUCCGAGCGUCAGCUCACUCCCCUUCCACCCUCAGCUCCACCCUCAGCAGAUGAUAAUAUCAAGACACCUGCCGAGCGUCUGCGGGGGCCGCUUCCACCCUCAGCAGAUGAUAAUCUCAAGACACCUUCCGAGCGUCAGCUCACUCCCCUUCCACCCUCAGCUCCACCCUCAGCAGAUGAUAAUAUCAAGACACCUGCCGAGCGUCUGCGGGGGCCGCUUCCACCCUCAGCGGAUGAUAAUCUCAAGACACCUUCCGAGCGUCAGCUCACUCCCCUUCCACCCUCAGCUCCACCCUCAGCAGAUGAUAAUAUCAAGACACCUGCCGAGCGUCUGCGGGGGCCGCUUCCACCCUCAGCAGAUGAUAAUCUCAAGACACCUUCCGAGCGUCAGCUCACUCCCCUUCCACCCUCAGCUCCACCCUCAGCAGAUGAUAAUAUCAAGACACCUGCCGAGCGUCUGCGGGGGCCGCUUCCACCCUCAGCGGAUGAUAAUCUCAAGACACCUUCCGAGCGUCAGCUCACUCCCUUUCCACCCUCAGCUCCACCCUCAGCAGAUGAUAAUAUCAAGACACCUGCCGAGCGUCUGCGGGGAGCGUCUGCGGGGGCCGCUUCCACCCUCAGCGGAUGAUAAUCUCAAGACACCUUCCGAGCGUCAGCUCACUCCCCUUCCACCCUCAGCUCCACCCUCAGCAGAUGAUAAUAUCAAGACACCUGCCGAGCGUCUGCGGGGGCCGCUUCCACCCUCAGCGGAUGAUAAUCUCAAGACACCUUCCGAGCGUCAGCUCACUCCCCUUCCACCCUCAGCUCCACCCUCAGCAGAUGAUAAUAUCAAGACACCUGCCGAGCGUCUGCGGGGGCCGCUUCCACCCUCAGCGGAUGAUAAUCUCAAGACACCUUCCGAGCGUCAGCUCACUCCCCUUCCACCCUCAGCUCCACCCUCAGCAGAUGAUAAUAUCAAGACACCUGCCGAGCGUCUGCGGGGGCCGCUUCCACCCUCAGCCGAUGAUAAUCUCAAGACACCUCCCUUAGCUACUCAGGAGGCUGAGGCAGAAAAACCACGCAAACCCAAGAGGCAGAGGGCGGCUGAGAUGGAACCACCUCCCGAACCCAAGAGGCGGAGGGUCGGUGACGUGGAACCGUCACGCAAACCCAAGAGGCGGAGGGCCGCUGACGUGGAACCAUCAUCACCCGAACCCAAGAGGCGGAGGGUCGGUGAUGUGGAACCGUCACGCAAACCCAAGAGGCGGAGGGCCGCUGACGUGGAACCAUCAUCACCCGAACCCAAGAGGCGGAGGGUCGGUGACGUGGAACCGUCACGCAAACCCAAGAGGCGGAGGGCCGCUGACGUGGAACCAUCAUUACCCGAACCCAAGAGGCGGAGGUUGAGCUGAGAAGAGGCCAGUGCACUCAAGCCUGAGCAAUAAGAAUAAAACCGAGUAGAACAAAAUAAAAAAUUCAAAAAACAAAACAAAACCCACACUCCAAAAACUAACAAAGAAUAAAUAAAUAAUAUAAAAAUAAAAUAAAUACUGCAGUCCUUA